AACGGAAGCUCCAGGAGCGCGGUGGAGCCUGGAGUGGAGGGCGAGGGUCCCACCGUGACCCGCCUGGAGGGCAGCCCAGCUCUGGGACGCGAAACCGCCUACGACGGUGCCGCAGCAGUUCCAAGAGCCUCUGAGUUCCUGCCUUUUUUCAUCUCUGAAUCCCCACCAUUGGCCUACAUUGGGAGUGGGGCGACCUAUGGGGAAAGCAAGGUCCUGAGACUCUGAGCAACUUCCCCAAGAUCACACAGCUAGGAAGUGAUGAAGCUGAGACAAGACCAGCCAGCACUUACCCACCACGGUGUGAUGCUGACGUUAGAGGACAAGGACAUGAAGGGAUUCUCCUGGGCCAUAGUCCCAGCCUUAACCUCCCUAGGCUACCUGAUUAUACUGGUGGUCUCCAUCUUUCCCUUCUGGGUGCGACUGACAAACGAGGAGUCCCACGAAGUCUUUUUCAGUGGCCUAUUUGAGAACUGCUUCAAUGCCAAAUGCUGGAAGCCUCGACCCUUAUCCAUUUACAUCAUCCUCGGCCGGGUUUUCCUGCUCUCUGCAGUUUUCUUGGCUUUCGUCACCACCUUCAUCAUGAUGCCCUUUGCAUCCGAGUUCUUCCCGAGGACCUGGAAGCAAAACUUUGUGUUAGCCUGCAUCAGCUUCUUCACAGGGGCCUGUGCCUUCCUGGCUUUGGUGCUGCAUGCCCUGGAGAUCAAGGCUCUGAGGAUGAAGCUCGGCCCCCUGCAGUUCUCCGUGCUGUGGCCUUACUACGUGCUGGGCUUCGGCAUCUUUCUGUUCAUAGUGGCUGGUACCAUCUGCCUCAUUCAAGAAAUGGUUUGCCCUUGCUGGCACUUGUUGUCCACUUCCCAGAGUAUGGAGGAGGACCACGGGAGCCUGUACCUGGACAAUCUGGAGAGUUUGGGAGGAGAACCGAGCUCAGUACAAAAGGAGACACAGGUGACAGCAGAAACAGUCAUCUAGCCCAGGACAUGGCUUCUUUACCCUUCUUCAAGCCAUGUGAGUGUACACAUGUAGCUGUUUGUAGUCCUCCCCACCCUCUCUGCCAGUAUCUGUGCCUUUGAGGAGCUUCUUGCGUGUCAGAUCAACUCUCCACCUCCCCAUACUCACAGUGAUUCUAUCUUGCUUGUAUGUGAAAUUUGCUAAAAGUCCUUUCAACUCUUCUGAGCUUCCUAAGUGACGUUUUUGCAGGUAUUUUCAAUAAAAAGAAGGGCUACUUUGUUCAUCCAUAUCUCAAAAACCAAGUCCGCAGGGCAGGAGGGGAGGGAGGAAUAUUACAAGAUAACCAAGUGAAAUGGGAUUUUGUGAAACAGAAACCGUACAGAAUACAGAAUAUACUCGGGGGAAUGACAACUAUUUGGGCUGGUGGCACAGGGGUAAAAGAAUUUACCAAGACGGUUGUAGAUAAAGAAAGGCAGAUUUAUUAAAGGAAGUAUAAAAGUA